AAGCCACAUAAACAAAGGCACAUUGGCGGCCAGGGCCAGUCCGCCCGGCGGCUCGCGCACGGCUCCGCGGUCCCUUUUGCCUGUCCAGCCGGCCGCCUGUCCCUGCUCCCUCCCUCCGUGAGGUGUCCGGGUUCCCUUCGCCCAGCUCUCCCACCCCUACCCGACCCCGGCGCCCGGGCUCCCAGAGGGAACUGCACUUCGGCAGAGUUGAAUGAAUGAAGACAGACGCGGAGAACUCCUAAGUGAGUAGAUGCAGCCCAUGCAGUUCGCCUUCUUUUAUGCUUUUUCCUUCUUUUGCACGUCUCUUCUUUCCACUUGUGUGGGACAGGUUCUCUGGAAGUGGGAGCCAGAGGCUUCUAGUGAGAGUGGGACCGAAGGAUGGGGAGUGCGUGCGCGCAGUUACCGGGGGGCAUUUGUUCGAACUCCGGCUUUGGCACUAGUGGGGAGUUGGCUCUCGACAGAGGUUUCCAGGCUCCUCAUUGGUGGACGUGGAAGGGAGACUCCACAGUUUGGGAGCUGAGGACUAGCCCGCGGAAAUGUGCGCAAAGUUUGCUGUUAGUGAGGAAUUGAUUGUGGCCUGUGAACACGGAGACUCCAAGUCCUAUGUAUACGAGGGAAGCUGCCCACAAACUGACAGGGAGAGGAAGUUCUUCAGUUUAUGCGUUGCUUGGGAACUGUGUCUCCGCGGCUGGCCAGCGCGCGAUGUUUCCCGGGUAUUGUUGAGUAAGGGUGGUGUUGGUAGCGUGUCCUGUUACUAAGUUGCCUGAAAUUUCUGGUUUUGACAUAUGCUGUCCUUGGGUUUGCGAAUGUAUCAGAGCGAGAAUAUGAAUAUGUAAAGAGUACAGUUAUGAAACUGUGGAGCUACCAGGGGGUUAAUAUCCAACACAGGAAUAUCUCUAAGGGCUGUGGGGUUCGAGUCUCCUUUCUGCUUUUUCUGGGUAAUCUUCCCCCCACCCCCACCACCACUAUGAAGCAAGAUUGUGGGGGAGGGGAAAGAAUAAAAAGAGAGGAUACUGGCUUUCUUUUUUCAUUAGUAAUAAGAUUGUCUGUGCUCUAGAAUGUCUUCCAAGUGGGAACAUCUGAAAAUUGCUAGGACACAAGAAUGCCUUGUUCCAGAAAGGCAGAUUGUGGAAGGCAUUAUGGGGAAGGUGUUCAUCUUGCUGUGCUGGGAAACACUUCUAAUAUUGGUGCCAAUACCAUAUAAGCAGUAUGUCCCCCCUCUGCAAUUGACCUAAGAAGCUCCUGGAAAAGUAGAUCCCCUCUUCCCACCUUGUGACCAUUAAGCCUUGUGACCAUUAAAGAUGCUGAAAGACAAGUUUUCUGGAAAAGUGAACAUCAAUUUAUCUGUAGCUCCAAUCCCAGUGCUCUGUCAAAAGCACUUUAGAAGUGCGGAUGCUUCCACUCAACUUGCCUUCUCAGUCAAGGCCUUUCUAACAUUUUGUAAGGGGGAAGAUUGUUUUCUCAUUUUAUAUUCUUGACUUCUACUUUCUUCCCCUCUACCAAAAGAAAAGGCAAUUUCACCACAAGAAAAAAAAAUGCAAGAGAAGGUUCCAAUGCUGUAUUUUCAUACUCUAGUCUUCAUACUCAGGUCCUGAAUUAACCUAAGAUGGAAAUGACCUCUCCACCUACACUGUAGCAAAGGGGCCAGUUCAUUACAUCAUAAAUGUUAAAUGAGUUCAUGGACUAGCUUUCCUCUUGCAGGAUCUUCUCUCUGCAAGGAUUUACACAGUGCAAUGGGUGGUAUUUUCUGUUGUUUCAAGUCAUUUCUUUUAUACAUUCAUUUUAAGUGCUAUGUUUGGUAAAGGCUUCCCACUCAUUUCCAAUGAGACAAACAGGGAAGGCAUGGAAGGGCCUGCCUGGUGAGUCUACAUAUGCCCAGCUGAAUCUCUGUCGGGAAGAAACCCUGAAGCUUCCUGUGUCUGUAUUUCAGGGAGGAGAUUGGACAGGCUGGACUCCCCAUUGCUUUUCUAAAAAUCUUGGAAACUUUGUCCUUCAUUGAAUUACGACACUGUCCACCUUUAAUUUCCUCGAAAACGCCUGUAACUCGGCUGAAGGUUAGUGCAACUUCAUUUCUUUCCUUUACUCUCCAGAGCUCCCCAAACAUCAAGAAACAGGACAAGGCAAACCCUGUAACUUAAGGUUUGCCCGACCCAUCGCCUUCGGGAACAACUUUCUCAUUGUGAAAUUCAACUUCAUUUCUAGAUGGUCAUUUCUAGAAAGAGACUGCUGAAUCUGAGCUUCAGAGAAGAGGCUCAUCUGAGUGGGAUGAGUGGGGGGGUAUGAGGGAGAUGUUUGGAAAUACCCAGGAGUGUAGACCCUCAGUAGCUUUUUAGCUCUGGGUCUUUAUUUGGUUAGUCUUUCCACGCCCUAAACUGUUGUUCUGCAGCAUUCUCUCUCUCCUGCCUUUCCUCUCGCGCCCCUACAUGCUCUCUGACUGCCGCGGGCUGCCGGUGUAGCUCCAGGUGUACCCGAGCCCGGGAGAAAGUGUUCAGUUGACCAGGCUGAGUGUGUUAUCACCCUGUUUCAUUUCCAGCCAUGCCUUGUGUUCAGGCGCAGUAUGGGUCCUCGCCUCAAGGAGCCAGCCCCGCUUCUCAGAGCUACAGUUACCACUCUUCGGGAGAAUACAGCUCCGAUUUCUUAACUCCAGAGUUUGUCAAGUUUAGCAUGGACCUCACCAACACUGAAAUCACUGCCACCACUUCUCUCCCCAGCUUCAGUACCUUUAUGGACAACUACAGCACAGGCUACGACGUCAAGCCACCUUGCUUGUACCAAAUGCCCCUGUCCGGACAGCAGUCCUCCAUUAAGGUAGAAGACAUUCAGAUGCACAACUACCAGCAACACAGCCACCUGCCCCCCCAGUCUGAGGAGAUGAUGCCGCACUCCGGGUCGGUUUACUACAAGCCCUCCUCGCCCCCGACGCCCACCACCCCGGGCUUCCAGGUGCAGCACAGCCCCAUGUGGGACGACCCGGGAUCUCUCCACAACUUCCACCAGAACUACGUGGCCACUACGCACAUGAUCGAGCAGAGGAAAACGCCAGUCUCCCGCCUCUCCCUCUUCUCCUUUAAGCAAUCGCCCCCUGGCACCCCGGUGUCUAGUUGCCAGAUGCGCUUCGACGGGCCCCUGCACGUCCCCAUGAACCCGGAGCCCGCCGGCAGCCACCACGUGGUGGACGGGCAGACCUUCGCUGUGCCCAACCCCAUUCGCAAGCCCGCGUCCAUGGGCUUCCCGGGCCUGCAGAUCGGCCACGCGUCUCAGCUGCUCGACACGCAGGUGCCCUCACCGCCGUCGCGGGGCUCCCCCUCCAACGAGGGGCUGUGCGCUGUGUGUGGGGACAACGCGGCCUGCCAACACUACGGCGUGCGCACCUGUGAGGGCUGCAAAGGCUUCUUUAAGCGCACAGUGCAAAAAAAUGCAAAAUACGUGUGUUUAGCAAAUAAAAACUGCCCAGUGGACAAGCGUCGCCGGAAUCGCUGUCAGUACUGCCGAUUUCAGAAGUGCCUGGCUGUUGGGAUGGUCAAAGAAGUGGUUCGCACAGACAGUUUAAAAGGCCGGAGAGGUCGUUUGCCCUCGAAACCGAAGAGCCCACAGGAGCCCUCUCCCCCUUCGCCCCCGGUGAGUCUGAUCAGUGCCCUCGUCAGGGCCCAUGUCGACUCCAACCCGGCUAUGACCAGCCUGGACUAUUCCAGGUUCCAGGCGAACCCUGACUAUCAAAUGAGUGGAGAUGACACCCAGCAUAUCCAGCAAUUCUAUGAUCUCCUGACUGGCUCCAUGGAGAUCAUCCGGGGCUGGGCAGAGAAGAUCCCUGGCUUCGCAGACCUGCCCAAAGCCGACCAAGACCUGCUUUUUGAAUCAGCUUUCUUAGAACUGUUUGUCCUUCGAUUAGCAUACAGGUCCAACCCAGUGGAGGGUAAACUCAUCUUUUGCAAUGGGGUGGUCUUGCACAGGUUGCAAUGCGUUCGUGGCUUUGGGGAAUGGAUUGAUUCCAUUGUUGAAUUCUCCUCCAACUUGCAGAAUAUGAACAUCGACAUUUCUGCCUUCUCCUGCAUUGCUGCCCUGGCUAUGGUCACAGAGAGACACGGGCUCAAGGAACCCAAGAGAGUGGAAGAACUGCAAAACAAGAUUGUAAAUUGUCUCAAAGACCACGUGACUUUCAACAAUGGGGGGUUGAACCGCCCCAAUUAUUUGUCCAAACUGUUGGGGAAGCUCCCAGAACUUCGUACCCUUUGCACACAGGGGCUACAGCGCAUUUUCUACCUGAAAUUGGAAGACUUGGUGCCACCGCCAGCAAUAAUUGACAAACUUUUCCUGGACACUUUACCUUUCUAAGACCUCCUCCCAAGCACUUCAAAGGAACUGGAAUGAUAAUGGAAACUGUCAAGAGGGGGCAAGUCACAUGGGCAGAGAUAGCCGUGUGAGCAGUCUCAGCUCAAGCUGCCCCCCAUUUCUGUAACCCUCCUAGCCCCCUUGAUCCCUAAAGAAAACAAACAAACAAACAAAAACUGUUGCUAUUUCCUAACCUGCAGGCAGAACCUGAAAGGGCAUUUUGGCUCCGGGGCAUCCUGGAUUUAGAACAUGGACUACACACAAUACAGUGGUAUAAACUUUUUAUUCUCAGUUUAAAAAUCAGUUUGUUGUUCAGAAGAAAGAUUGCUAUAAUGUAUAAUGGGAAAUGUUUGGCCAUGCUUGGUUGUUGCAGUUCAGACAAAUGUAACACACACACACAUACACACACACACACACACACAGAGACACAUCUUAAGGGGACCCACAAGUAUUGCCCUUUAACAAGACUUCAAAGUUUUCUGCUGUAAAGAAAGCUGUAAUAUAUAGUAAAACUAAAUGUUGCGUGGGUGGCAUGAGUUGAAGAAGGCAAAGGCUUGUAAAUUUACCCAAUGCAGUUUGGCUUUUUAAAUUAUUUUGUGCCUAUUUAUGAAUAAAUAUUACAAAUUCUAAAAGAUAAGUGUGUUUGCAAAAAAAAAGAAAAUAAAUACAUAAAAAAGGGACAAGCAUGUUGAUUCUAGGUUGAAAAUGUUAUAGGCACUUGCUACUUCAGUAAUGUCUAUAUUAUAUAAAUAGUAUUUCAGACACUAUGUAGUCUGUUAGAUUUUAUAAAGAUUGGUAGUUAUCUGAGCUUAAACAUUUUCUCAAUUGUAAAAUAGGUGGGCACAAGUAUUACACAUCAGAAAAUCCUGACAAAAGGGACACAUAGUGUUUGUAACACCGUCCAACAUUCCUUGUUUGUAAGUGUUGUAUGUACCGUUGAUGUUGAUAAAAAGAAAGUUUAUAUCUUGAUUAUUUUGUUGUCUAAAGCUAAACAAAACUUGCAUGCAGCAGCUUUUGACUGUUUCCAGAGUGCUUAUAAUAUACAUAACUCCCUGGAAAUAACUGAGCACUUUGAAUUUUUUUUAUGUCUAAAAUUGUCAGUUAAUUUAUUAUUUUGUUUGAGUAAGAAUUUUAAUAUUGCCAUAUUCUGUAGUAUUUUUCUUUGUAUAUUUCUAGUAUGGCACAUGAUAUGAGUCACUGCCUUUUUUUCUAUGGUGUAUGACAGUUAGAGAUGCUGAUUUUUUUUCUGAUAAAUUCUUUCUUUGAGAAAGACAAUUUUAAUGUUUACAACAAUAAACCAUGUAAAUGAA